UUUCUUUUUCUUUUUCAUAAAUUGAGACAGGAUGUUGCUAUGUUGCCCAGGCUGGUCUUGAAGUGCCUUGACCUCCUAAAGUGUUGGAACCACAGACGUGAGCCACUCCACCCAGCCUAAAACUUCAUCUUCUUUGAUGGAGGCUUGCUCUGUGGCCCAGGCUGGAGUACACUGGCAUGAUCUUGGCUUACUGCAACCUCUCCCUCUUGGUUCAACUGAUUCUCCUGCCUCAGCCUCCCGAGUAGCUGGGAUUACUGGAUGAGAUGAACACUUUUAACAAGAGAACAGGACUCUAUAUAAAUCGCUGUGGGCUCACCACCUCUAAGGAGGAGCACUGACUGAAGACAGAAAAAUUGAUGAACUGAAGAAGACAUGGUCCAUUAUGCCUUACAAACUUACACAGUGCUUUGGGAAUUCCAAAGUACUCAGUGGAGAGAGGUGUUUCAGGAGCCGUAGAGCCAGAUCGUCAUCAUGUCUGCAUUGUGGCUGCUGCUGGGCCUCCUUGCCCUGAUGGACUUGUCUGAAAGCAGCAACUGGGGAUGCUAUGGAAACAUCCAAAGCCUGGACACCCCUGGAGCAUCUUGUGGGAUUGGAAGACGUCACGGCCUGAACUACUGUGGAGUUCGUGCUUCUGAAAGGCUGGCUGAAAUAGACAUGCCAUACCUCCUGAAAUAUCAACCCAUGAUGCAAACCAUUGGCCAAAAGUACUGCAUGGAUCCUGCCGUGAUCGCUGGUGUCUUGUCCAGGAAGUCUCCCGGUGACAAAAUUCUGGUCAACAUGGGCGAUAGGACUAGCAUGGUGCAGGACCCUGGCUCUCAAGCUCCCACAUCCUGGAUUAGUGAGUCUCAGGUUUCCCAGACAACUGAAGUUCUGACUACUAGAAUCAAAGAAAUCCAGAGGAGGUUUCCAACCUGGACCCCUGACCAGUACCUGAGAGGUGGACUCUGUGCCUACAGUGGGGGUGCUGGCUAUGUCCGAAGCAGCCAGGACCUGAGCUGUGACUUCUGCAAUGAUGUCCUUGCACGAGCCAAGUACCUCAAGAGACAUGGCUUCUAACAUCUCAGAUGAAACCCAAGACCAUGAUCACAUAUGCAGCCUCAAAUGUUACACAGAUAAAACUAGCCAAGGGCACCUGUAACUGGGAAUCUGAGUUUGACCUAAAAGUCAUUAAAAUAACAUGAAUCACAUUAAAGGAAGAAUUUUGACCUGCA